AGCCAGUUUCUCAAGGACUAGGAAGUAGCGUCAUUCUGAGAUCUCAGCCAUUUCGAUAAAAAAUAGAUAUAAGAAAUAGGACAGAAAAUGUCAGAUCGUAUGUGCGUUCUAGACCGCUGAUUCGUCGAUUUGUAAAACAAGAGAAGGAUAAGAUGGUUUCCAGAUGUAGCUGCCUGGGGGUCCAGUGUCUGCUGCUCUCGCUUCUUCUCCUCGCAGCCUGGGAGGUGGGGAGCGGCCAGCUCCACUACUCAGUCUACGAGGAGGCCAGACACGGCACCUUCGUGGGCCGCAUCGCGCAGGACCUGGGGCUGGAGCUGGCGGAGCUGGUGCAGCGCCUGUUCCGGGUGGCGUCCAAAAGACACGGGGACCUUCUGGAGGUAAAUCUGCAGAAUGGCAUUUUGUUUGUGAAUUCUCGGAUUGACCGCGAGGAGCUGUGCGGGCGGAGCGUGGAGUGCAGCAUCCACCUGGAGGUGAUCGUGGACAGGCCGCUGCAGGUUUUCCAUGUGGACGUGGAAGUGAAGGACAUUAACGACAACCCGCCCAGGUUCUCCGUAACAGAACAAAAGCUCUCAAUACCUGAAUCCAGACUGCUUGACUCUCGAUUUCCACUAGAAGGCGCAUCUGAUGCGGAUGUUGGAGAGAACGCAUUGCUUACUUACAAACUCAGUCCAAAUGAGUAUUUUGUUCUUGAUAUUAUAAACAAAAAAGACAAAGACAAAUUCCCAGUGCUUGUUCUGCGGAAGCUGCUGGAUCGUGAAGAAAAUCCUCAGCUAAAGUUGUUGUUGACAGCAACUGAUGGAGGCAAACCUGAAUUUACCGGAUCUGUUUCUCUGCUGAUCCUGGUGUUAGAUGCCAAUGAUAACGCCCCUAUCUUUGACAGACCGGUUUAUGAAGUUAAGAUGUAUGAAAAUCAAGUGAACCAAACAUUAGUAAUACGGCUCAACGCUUCUGAUUCGGAUGAAGGAAUAAACAAGGAAAUGAUGUAUUCAUUUAGCUCUUUGGUCCCACCCACGAUAAGAAGGAAAUUUUGGAUAAACGAAAGGACGGGAGAAAUAAAAGUAAAUGAUGCUAUUGACUUUGAGGACAGUAACACUUAUGAAAUUCAUGUAGAUGUUACAGAUAAGGGAAACCCACCUAUGGUUGGUCACUGCACGGUCCUAGUGGAACUACUGGAUGAAAAUGAUAAUUCACCUGAGGUGAUUGUCACUUCUCUGUCUCUCCCAGUGAAAGAAGAUGCUCAAGUGGGCACCGUCAUUGCCCUAAUCAGCGUUUCUGACCAUGAUUCAGGAGCCAACGGACAGGUCACCUGCUCUCUGACGCCUCACGUUCCGUUCAAGCUGGUGUCCACCUACAAGAAUUACUACUCAUUGGUGCUGGACAGCGCUCUGGACCGCGAGAGGGUGUCGGCCUAUGAGCUGGUGGUGACCGCGCGGGACGGGGGCUCGCCUCCGCUGUGGGCCACGGCCAGCGUGUCUGUGGAGGUGGCCGACGUGAACGACAACGCGCCUGCGUUCGCGCAGUCCGAGUACACGGUGUUCGUGAAGGAGAACAACCCGCCAGGCUGCCACAUCUUCACGGUGUCUGCGUGGGACGCGGACGCGCAGGAGAACGCCCUGGUGUCCUACUCUCUGGUGGAGCGGCGGUUGGGCGAGCGCUCGCUGUCGAGCUACGUGUCGGUGCACGCGGAGAGCGGCAAGGUGUACGCGCUGCAGCCGCUGGACCACGAGGAGCUGGAGCUGCUACAGUUCCAGGUGAGCGCGCGCGAUGGGGGCGUGCCGCCUCUGGGCAGCAACUUGACGCUGCAGGUGUUCGUGCUGGACGAGAACGACAACGCUCCCGCGCUGCUGGCGUCUCCCGCUGGCAGCGCGGGCGGUGCAGUCAGUGAGCUGGUGCUGCGGUCGGUGGUUGCGGGUCACGUGGUGGCUAAGGUGCGCGCAGUGGACGCUGACUCUGGAUACAACGCGUGGCUGUCGUAUGAAUUGCAGUCGGCGGCGGUUGGUGCACGCAUCCCGUUUCGCGUGGGGCUGUACACGGGCGAGAUCAGUACGACGCGCGCUCUGGAUGAGACUGACUCGCCACGCCAGCGCCUACUGGUGCUGGUGAAGGACCAUGGCGAGCCGUCGCUGACGGCCACGGCCACUGUGCUUGUGUCGCUUGUGGAGGGCAGCCAGGCACCCAAGGCCUCGUCGCGGGCUUCAGUGGGCGUGGCGCCCGAGGUGGCCCUGGUGGAUGUCAACGUGUACCUGAUCAUCGCCAUCUGCGCGGUGUCCAGCUUGCUGGUGCUCACGCUGCUGCUGUACACUGCACUGAGGUGCUCGGCGGCGCCCACCGAGGGCGCAUGUGGGCCGGUGAAGCCCACGCUGGUGUGCUCUAGCGCGGUGGGGAGCUGGUCUUACUCGCAGCAGAGGCGGCAGAGGGUGUGUUCUGGGGAGGGCCUGCCCAAGGCGGACCUCAUGGCCUUCAGCCCCAGCCUUCCACCAUGCCCAAUGGUAGAUGUGGACGGGGAAGAUCAGUCUAUUGGAGGGGACCACUCUAGGAAGGUGGGUUAUUACGUUUUCAUUUUCCUUUUGUGCUUUAUGAAUAAUAUUUUCUCUUACCGCAUUUUCUCAAAUAUGUAUCAGAAUAUUUCAUUUUUGUCUACAUUCCAUUUAUGCUUGAAUAUUUCUAGUGAUACCUUUGUAAUAUAAUUUAUUCCAGGAGUUUUAAAAUUUUUUUAUCCUACCCAGUGUGUCAGCCUUUGAUUGGUACUUAAAUUUUUUUAAAUAACAAUUUAUUCUGAAUACACUAAUAUUUUCCAAUACAAAUAUGUGAUAUAGGUUGCAGUUCUGACGAUUUACUUUCAUAAUCACUUUUCGUUACAAAUAUUUGUGAGAUUAGUACUUCAUGUUAUUUCAUUUCCAAUCUAAAUUUUGAUUUGAUUGUAUUUGCAUUACCAAAAAAUUCCACUGAUCUAUAUCUCUUCAGUGAAAAUGUGUUUUCCUCCAUGUGUAGAAUAUGUGUAGCGUACCACAGCUUAUACUGCCAUAGUAGAUUUCAAUGUUCAGUGAUUACAGCUUUUUCUCAAUAGUGCAGUAAGUAGGUGGGCAGUUCAUUGGUAAAAAUUUCUUAAUCUUAGCAAUUAAGUUAAAUGCUUUGAACUUUAAAAACGUUUUCCAUUUUUAUUUUAGUUGUAGUGGUACCUGUGUCAGUGUGUAUUAUUCACUUAGCAGAAGAAAAUGUAUGUUUCUUUUAUUUACAUAAUUUUAUCCAGUAGCUCUUCAUUAUCUGCUCCUUUAUCAGCAUUAGGCAUUGCUUAUGAUAUUCAGGUAUUAGCUCUUUCACUUUAAGGAAGGAGUCAUGCUUAUGUUUAAUAAUGAAGAGAAUUUGAACACUUUUUACUUUUGAGACUGAAAAUACUUUAGUAUGAAUUAAUAUUAAAAGUUUGAGGAGAAAAUAAAAUUAAUGUUUUCUACUGAUCUGAUAUAUUGUAUAGUUUAAUAGCUUCUCUAGUCAUCUUAAACAGGGUUGGGUUAGAUGAUAUAGACUCAGAAAUGAAAGCUAACUUAGUUGCAGAGUGACAAAACUACACUAUCAAUUGUGUUUUCCUGAAAUUGGUUGUUACCUGAUACCCAUGAUUUCAUUUUUAAAAAAAAUUUAUUAAUUCUAGUGUUACCAAACACCAAUGCCAUGAAUUUGUCAUCUUGCCUAUGGCUCUUAGCAAUUACUUUUUUCUUUCCUUUCUCUUUGAGUAUGGAGAUUGAAUUUGUUACUCAGUACGUGCUUCACAAAUAGCUUCAAAUAAAAUUAAAAUUAUUGUUCAAGUUUAGGAACACCAAAAAAAAAUUGUGGCAAGAAUUUAAGCAUGGCAUUCUUUCAGUGUUAAUACUCUCCAUGCCCUGUCUCCAGCUCUUAGAAAUUAUAGAUGCUAAGUUAAUGCAGAGUUUAGAAGUGUAUUUGUUAUUUUAUCAAAUAGGUUUAUGAAAUAUAUACUUCCCCCUCUGAUAUUUUGAAAAAAAAUCUUCCUUAAUGUCUUAUAUUAUAAGUAAUAUAAAAAACUUAGUAAAAACUCAUAUCAAUUGUAAAAGUCUCAGGUAUACAAGUGCAUUAAUCUCUCCAUCAAUACUAACUUAAGGCCAGGCAUGGUGGCUCACACCUGUAAUCCCAGCAUUUUGAGAGGCCAAGGUGGGAGGAUGGUUUGAGGCCAGGAGUUCAAGACCAACCUGGGCGACAUAGGGAUAUCUUGUACUGUGUGUGUGUGUAUAUAUAUGUAUAUAUGUGUAUAUAUAUAUGUAUAUAUAUAUGAUGGGCUCUCCUUACAUAUAUAUCUAUAUAUGUACUUAUGUAUAUAUAAGCCAGGCAUGGUGGUACAUGCCUUUAGUCCCUACUGUAGUGCUACUUGGGAGGGUGAGGUGGGAGGACGGCUUGAGCCUGGGAAGUUGAGGCUGCAGUGACCCAUGAUUGUGCCACUGCACUCCAGCCUGGAUGACAAAGUGAGACCCUAUUUCAAAAAUUGAAAAAAGCAAAAGCAAUAGUAACACCAUUAUCCUGCAAAUAUGAUCUUUUUCAUAUUAAUUCACGUGAUAAUACAGUUGGUGCAGUAGUACUUUAUUUAGGAUGUCUACAUACAAGAUAAAACUCUUCAUGGAAUUCUGAUUUGUAAGACAAACCCACCUUUGAAGAGGUACUGAUCAUACACAAGAAGGUAUAGGAAAGGAGUUGGAAGCUCACAAAGAGAAACAUAAACAUAUGCAGGAAUCAGGAACGAAGAAGAUAAGUGAAAUAAUAUGAAAUCAAAUGCACUUAUGUUUUGAGCGACAGGAUAUUGUUGUUCUCCAUGAAAAGUUUUUUUGGUUUUUUUGUUUUUUAUUUUUUAUUUUUUUGAGACGGAGUCUCGCUCUGUUGCCCAGGCUGGAGUGCAGUGGCACGAUCUCGGCUCACUGCAAGCUCCGCCUCCCAGGUUCACGCUAUUCUCCUGCCUCAGCCUCCGGAGUAGCUGGGACUACAGGUGCCCGCCAACACGCCAGGCUAAUUUUUUGUAUUUUUAGUAGAGACGAGGUUUCACCGUGUUAGCCAGGAUGGUCUAGAUCUCCUGACCUCGUGAUCCACCGGCCUCGGCUUCCCAAAGUGCUGGCCGAGUGCCACCGCACCCGGCCGAAAGGUAUUUUUUUUAACAGAAGAAAAUCAGAUUAUUCCUAGAUCAGAAAGAAGCUCCAUUGUUCCUGUACUUUAAAAACUACAAACACCCAUUAAGACCACUUGGAACCUCAGGAACAAGGACCAAAAGGUCUCAGAGGAACUAAGUCUUUCUAGUCAUGAAAUAUUGUUUUACUAACCAAAAGAGAGGCAUAAUUUUAGCUGCUAGACAAAGUGGCCAGGAAUCCCGGAGCCUACAGCACUGGCUUCUGCUCCUUGAAUUUUGUGAAGCGGGAAAGGACCAGUUCCACUACACCAUCCUGGAAGAGGCCAAGGACGGCACAUAGCGUCUUCGCGGUCCCUAUUGCGCAGGACCUGGGUCUGGAGCUUGUGGAGCUGAUACCGCGCCUGUUUCAGUUGGAUUCCAAAAGCCGCAGAAACCUUCUGGAGGUAAAUCUGCAGAAUGGCAUUUUUGUGAGUUCUCUGAUAGACCUCGAGGAGCUGUGUGGGAGGAUCUCGGAGUGCAGCAUCCACCUGGAAGUGAUCGUGGACAAGCUGCUACAGGUUUUCCAUGUGGAGGUGAAAGUGAAGAACAAUAAAGACAACCUGCCAGUGUUCUCAGCAACACAAAAGAAUCUGUUUCUGAAACGAGAGCUCUUGAUUAUCGUGUUUCACUAGAGGGUGUCUGUGAUGCCGACGUCGGGGCCAAUGCUCUGAUGACUUACAUACUGUGCCGCAAUGAUUAUUUUUCCCUGGAAAUACCAAGAGCAGGUAAAACCACUUGAAGGUGUAUUUUAAAAAUUCUUUCAGAUAGGUAAGUCACUUCAGAGCUACUCUUGGUGCUCAAAGCAACUGAUGGGGGCGAAGCUGAGCUGACAGGCACCAAAGCAUUAUAUAUCACAGCGCUGGAUGUAAAUGAUGAUGCCCAGUGUUUGACAAAGGAGUCUAUCAUGUGAAAUUACUGGAAAAUGCAAGAGAAGGUACACUGGUUAUUAGACUUAACCCCUUGGAUUUUGACGAGGGUUCAAACCGUCACAUUGUUUCUUUGCAACUGAUGUCUCCCCUAACAUAGAAGCCCUUUUUCGCAUAGAUUCAGACAGUGGAUAAAUAAAUGUAAAGAUAGGUUUUGAGGAAACUAAAUAAUGAAAGAUUCAAAUACAGGCAGUUGACACAGGCAAUUCCCCAAUGUUUGAUCACUGCACAGACUUGAUAGAAGUCUUGGACAUCAAUGAUAGUGUUCCAGAGUUAGCAGUAAGUCACUAUCAUUCCCUGUACAGGAGGACGCUCCACUGGGUACCGUCAUAGCCCUAAUCAGUGUAAUUGACCCUAACUUCAGUGCCAAGGGACAGACGACCCGCACCCUGACUCCUCACGUCUCUUCAAGCUGGUGUCUACCUUCAAAAGGCGCUGCCCAGAAACUAUUCGUUGGUACUCCACAGCGCCCUGGACCAAGAGAGCAAAUCUAUCCAUUGUUGGUAAUCGCUCGGAAUGGGGACUCGCUUUCAUUGUUGGCCACAGCCAUCGGGUCCGUGGAAGUGGCCGAACAGUGAACCACAAUGCCCUGGCGUUCCAGCAGCCCGAGUACAUGGUGUUCGUGAAAGGUAACAACCCGCGGGGCUGCCACGACUUCACAGUGUCCGCGCGGGACCGGGACGCGCAGGAGAACGUGCUGGUGUCCUACUCGUUGAUGGAACAGCGGGUGGGCGAGUGCGCGCUGUCUAGCUAUGUGUGGGUGCACGCGGAGAGCGGCAAGAGGUACGCGUUGCAGCCACUGGACUACGAGGAGCUGGAGCUGCUGCAGUUCUAGGUGAGAGCGCGCGACGCGGGCAUGCCGCCUCUGAGCAGCAAUGUGACGCUGCCAGGUAUUAGUGCUGGAACGACAACUUUGUCUGCGCUGCUGGCGCCUUGGGUGGGCUGGCGGCGCUGUGAGUGAGCUGGUGCGGUAUUCAGUGGAUGCAGGCCACUUGGUGGCGAAGGUGCGCACGGUGGACUCCAGCUAUGACGCCUGGUUGUCGCAACAGCUGCAUCUGUCAGCUGGCAGCACCCGUUCCACGUGGGGCUCUGCACGGGCGAGAUCAGCACGACGAGUACCCUGGACGAGGCGAAAGCUACGCGCCACCGCCUGCUGGUGCUGGUGAAGGACCACUGCGAGCUGGCGCUGACUGCCACCGUCACCGUGGUGGCGUCGCUGGCGGAGAGCAGCCAAGCGAGGAAGGUCCCAUCGCGGGCUUUGGCGGGCGUCGAGGUCCGGGAGGCAGCGCUGGUGGAUGUCAACGUGUACCUGAUCAUCGCCAUCUGCGUGGUGUCCAGCCUGUUAGUGCUCACGUUGCUGCUGUACACGACGCUGCGGUGCUUGGCGCAGCUCACCGAGAGCUCGUGCAUGCCGGGCAAGCCCACGCUGGUGUACCGCAGCGUAGUGGGAUCUGGUCUUACUCGCAGCAAAGGAGAUUUUACUCUGGAGAGUCGCCUCCCAAGGUCAACAUUACGGCUUUUAGUCCUAGUGUUCUCCCAUGGUUCAGAUUUUGGAGAUGGACUUCAAUAGGAAAUUUUUGAGAAUAUAAGUACUGUAAUCCUGGAAAGUAUUUCAUUCCUAUUAAUGUCCCUCAUAGUGACAUUGAUAAUGUUCACCAAGUUAUUAAUUUGAUUGCUUUAUUUAUUUUGCUUUUGCUUUUUCUUUUGAGAUGCUUUAUUUAAAGUACACUGGGGCCGGGUGCGGUAGCUCAUGCCUAUUUGUAAUCCCGGCACUUUGGGAAGCCGAGGCGGGCGGAUCACUCGAGGCCAGGAGUUUGAGACCAGCCUGGCCAACAUGGUGAAACUCCAUCUCUACUAAAGAUAUAAAAAAAUUAGCUGGGUGUGGUGGUGCGCACCUGUAAUCCCAGCUACUCAGGAGGCUGAGGCACAAGAAUUGCUUGAACCUAGGAGGCAGAGGUUGCGGUGAGCCUAGAUUAGGCCACUGCACUACAGCCUGGGAGACAGGGUGAAACUCUGUCUUAAAAAAAAAAGUACAUUGGAAGUCUAGCCAUCUUAAUCACUUUUUACUACAGUCACCAUGAACAUUCUUUAGGAAUAUUCUUCAGUUGAUAAGUAUAAUGAUAAUAGUAAUAAUGAAUUAGACUGAGUGGCUGUUUCCUGUAAAUGAGAAAGUUAAAUCUUACCGGAAGGAUCAUGAUGAAUAAUGAUCCUUAUGAGAAGGUCAAAUCUUCUCAAUUUUGAAGCAAGUUCUUUAUUCCUAUUCAUUUUCUUAUUCUGAUUUGUGUCCUCCAUUCCUUAUUGUUUUUAUGUAUUCAAAAAUACCAUGACAAUAUUUAAUAUCAUAAUUAUUUGAGUUUAAAACAUGUUUAAAUGUUUAUCUUUCUAUAAUCGAUAAGUUUAUCUCUCACAAAUGGUGAUGAGCAGGGUUGAGGCAGCUUCGUCCACAAACAAUUUUGUUUCUUCAUGAUCAAUAUCCAUCUUUUUUGAGAUGUUGAUUGCAGUGGGUGGAAUUUUAGCCUUGCCUUUAAAGGUGAUUUUACUUCUUAAUUUUUGUCUUCAAUCUUCUUAUAAUUUCAUUUUAGGUCAUUGUCUUCACAAUCUUCAACUACUUCAGAUAGCCAACAACUUUGUUCUUUUUUAAAAAGAAAACAAAACAAAACAAUGUCAGCUCUACUUAAUUACCUGUUGACUUAAUUGCUGCUGUCCUCCAGUUUAAGUUGUUGAGCUCUUCUACUAUUUUGGGAAGAUUUCUUUGAGCACCGAUUAUACUCAUUUUUCUUUCAUUUUUGGUACCUGGCUGUAUGAAAAUAUUUUAGGGUAGGAAAAUUCACACUUAUUUGGGCUUUAAGUAUAAGAGAGUCUUCCCAUACAUGAUGAAGGGUGAUACCAUUGUCUGUGUUCAUUAAGCUGCAUGGUCUUCAGAAUGGCAUUGCUGAGCUUGGCAGGGUGUCUCAGGCCUGUAAUCCCAGCAUUUUGGGAAGCCGAGGGAGGAGGAUCGCUUGAGACCAGGAGUUUGAGACCAGCCUCGGCAACAUAGUGAGACCCCCAUCUCUACCAAAAAAUGUCAUUGUUUUUAAUAACUUAAGUAUAAGAACCAUGGGAUAUUAAUAAAGGCACUUCCACUUGACAAUUGUGGUGUUAAUUAUACCUUAGAAUUUAACAUUGUAUACUUUUGAUAUAUUUGAUGCAAAAUAUUUUUUGCCUUCACACCAUAUUAAUGUGAAUUGCUUUCUUUAAAGGGAUCCCAGAGAACACGUAUUUAUAGCUGUAAGGAUGUGUAUCAAAUUAUAUGUAAAAUUACUUUGCUCUUUUUGGCUCUAAUUACAAAUGAGAUGGCCUUUAAUUCUGUGUAAAGAAAUAGUAUAUUUACAUAUUGCAGGAUAACCAUGUUAUAGGUAGGGUAAAGUUAAUAUAAAUGCUGAAAAGGAAUUAGUAGUGUCUACCUAGAAAAAUAACUUCUGAGAAGAUGAUUUCUAUGAAGAUAAACAUUAAGGAAAUCUUCAGAAAAGGGAAAACCCUGUCCUACUUUAUGGUGCUGGAAUUCUCUUCAUCCAUAGCUAUAGGACAAGAGCCAAUAUUGAUCAGUAACUCAUGAUAAUAAAUCACCAUUGUUUGAGCAGUUUAUUAAUAUAUUUGUUAGACAUCAUGAAGGGACUUAAAUACAUUAUUUCAUUUAAUACUUAUAACAAUUUCUAAAGUACAUAUGACUGUUCCAAUUUGAAAGAUAAAAUAAGAGAAGCUGAGAUGUGUAUCUAUUUUAUCCAGUGCCAGUACAUGGUGGAGAUAUUAUUCAAAUGUGUAUCUUUCAGGCUUCAGACUCAUUCUUUUAUCCACUAUAAUGUAGAGCUUUCUUUAGUAAGUCAUUUCUCUGCUCAAACAUGGUCUCGGCUAGGAAAAUCAAGCACAAAUUGUGUACAGGCAAAUCUUUCUUUCUGUUGUGCUUAGAAGAAACUUCAUGAUUGUCUUCAUCAUUAAUUUUGUACAAUGUGUGAUUGAGAUGGCACUAAGUUUUUUUAUGUUAAGUGAUUUUUUUCUUGUAAGAGUUCGUGAUCAUCAUUAUCAUUUGUUUUAAUCAAUGCCACACUGAGAUAGGUAUUUUGGUUAUGUAAUUGUUAAGUAAUUAAGAGUUGCCUUAUAAGAACUACGUAUCUGUUGUUUGGAAGUGAUAUAAGUAAGAAUCGUUUAACAUGUAAGAAAAGUCAGAAAACUGUGGUUUCCAAUAUCCUUGUGGAACACCUAAACUAAAUACUAUAUACCAAAAAUGACACCCUUCUUUCUUUACUGUGAAUAAAGACAGUGUUUGGGACAAGUAUAGAUGUUGAUAUUAUUAUUUCAGGGACCCUGAACUUGGCCAAAGGAUUCAAGAAAUGUUUACAAUAUUGCAUACUUCAAUAACAAUUUUAAAGACAUAGAUUCCCAUGAAAAUCUUCAAAUGUGUGUAGGUCUUUCAGUCUUCUUCAGUCUUAUUGUUGGCUGGGAAGCUCAUAACAACUGACAAAUGAUUUGUGACCAAAUAACUGUUUUUACUUGACUAAGCCAUGAUAGAGCAGAAUUAGCAUCACGGAAUAAAUCCUAUAAUUUUGUUAAUACAGUGGUUGGAUAAUGUAAUUCUAAUCUGUUGGUUUUGGAGAACCUCCUGGGGUUCUGACAACGGUGUCAAAAUUUAUUUAUGUGUUUUCAAGAAAUAAUAGCACUAGGUCUGUUAGAAUAUCAGUGGAUGACGUGCACUAGUAAGACAUUAAACUAUGCACUCUAAUACUUAUAUGACUAACAGGACAUACAGGCAGAUUGUAUGUCCUGACUGAUAUAGUAAAAGUCAGGCACAAAGUUCCUUAAUCUUCAAUUGAUUUUACAAAAUCAGUUAACAAUAACUGUAUUGAAAUGACUUCUUGGUAUUAGCCUAUACCCAGAUAUUAGGCUGAUCCUCAAAGAUGAGUUCAAAGGGCGCAUAAUCUCUUCACUAGGGGCUGGUUGAGAUGGUGACAUCUGAAAUAUCACAGCCAAAAUGCAAAAGAUGGGUCAUUGAUUCAUACACUAUAUCAAACUCUUUUAUGACUUGGCGUUUGUUCAGUACUACUUUAUAUAUUCACAAAAUACUGUAUUGUUGGAAAUUAACACCUAAAUUAACAUAUUGUUUUAAUUCAAAUAUGUGAUAUUAUCAUUUUUCCAGAGUAAACCUUCUAAGGUUCAUUUCCCUACCUCGCAAGACUCCACAUUCCAUGUAACAUCUUCAUCCCCAAUUCCCAUAAUAAGGUGAUUGAGGAUCUGUUGUUUCCUUUUGUUCAAAAUAAACCUGAUGUGCUUCAAAUAUCAUGUUGAAUAUACUGUCAUCUGGUCUAAUGUUAUGUUUUGAUUAGAGGCUACUAUGAUUGAUUAUUUUACAGAUGCGUAAUGGAAUUAACGGUUAUAAAAGUUGAUAUGUCUCCUUUAAUUUUUUAAUACAGAAUUUUGCAUUUACCUGAAUUAGAGUUCUAGUGUUAUGACAACAUUGGGAAAAGAGUAAAUAUGAAAAAAGUAGAACAAAAUCUCAAAUUAAUAGUUGAAUAUAUAUAUAAAAUAUUAGCAUACACAUAUGAUAACUUUUUCAUAUGCCCUUGCAGUAUUUUUAGAUUGGAGAUAAACCAUCAAAACUAUAGAACAAAAUAUUUAAGCUAGAGUGAUAUUUAUUCUAAAUCACUUUCUACUCUAAAAUUUUGUUGCAUCUUCUUUUUUUCCUCCUAAAUCCUAAGGGUAUAUGAAAAGACAAAGAAAAUUCAAGCAAGUUACAACUUCAGGCAAAGAAAACUCUCAUAAGCAAUUCCUGUAUUUUACUUAGCAUUUUCUAUGAAAUUCCAUUUCCACAAGCACUAAGGUAAUUUACCAUUUAGUUGAAUUGUUUGAUUAAUUUUCUAUGUUUUAAGCACAAUAUCAGGUACUUACAGAAGGUAUAAUUAAAAAUCACUUCCCUUGUUUUCCAUGAACUUCUGCUCCCAAACCCAAAAUUCUUUCAACAAGAAACAAACUAUUUUCAUGAAUAUAACUGAAUUAGAUUAAGGAAACCAAUGUUGGUGACUUGGAAAUACCAAUAUGGCACAAAGAUGUUCAGGGUGAUUUUAUUUAUUUUAUAAAAUGAUAAUAAAAUUUAUUUUAUAGUUGAAAAGCCUAUUUCUGUCAUAUCAUUGAUUCUGUUACAUAAAGUGCUAAAUUUUGAUAUCUCAUAUUAUGCUACUAUGGCUUACAUUAGAAAUAAUAUAUGUCAAAUAAAAACUCAUCUAGAUCAA